AGACUGUGCACGCUCCUGUCCCCACUCACAGGCCCACGCAGCGAGGGGGGCCCCUCUUCUGUGUGCGUCUGGAAGGUCGCUGCCCAGGGAGGAAAUGCCUUUAACCGGCGUGGGGCCGGGCAGCUGCAGGAGGCAGAUCAUCCGGGCUCUGUGCCUCUUGCUACUUCUCCUCCACGCCGGCUCUGCCAAGAAUAUCUGGAAACGGGCAUUGCCUGCGAGGCUGGCCGAGAAAUCCCGUGCCGAGGAGGCGGGCGCGCCCGGCGGCCCCCGGCAGCCCCGAGCAGACCGCUGCCCGCCGCCUCCGCGGACGCUGCCCCCCGGCGCCUGCCAGGCCGCGCGCUGUCAGGCGGACUCCGAGUGCCCGCGGCACCGGCGCUGCUGCUACAACGGAUGCGCCUACGCCUGCCUAGAAGCUGUGCCGCCCCCGCCAGUCUUAGACUGGCUGGUGCAGCCGAAACCUCGAUGGCUUGGUGGCAAUGGCUGGCUCCUGGAUGGCCCUGAGGAGGUGUUACAAGCAGAGGCGUGCAGCACCACGGAGGAUGGGGCCGAACCCCUGCUCUGUCCCUCGGGCUAUGAGUGCCACAUCCUGAGCCCAGGUGACGUGGCCGAAGGUAUCCCCAACCGUGGGCAGUGCGUCAAGCAGCGCCGGCAAGCAGAUGGGCGAAUCCUACGACACAAACUUUACAAAGAAUAUCCAGAAGGUGACUCAAAGAAUGUGGCAGAACCUGGAAGGGGACAACAGAAGCACUUUCAGUAAAGCAACGGCAAGCAGCUAGGUUGCAAGAACAUUCCUCUACUUUCUGCUAAGCCUUGGAAACAGUUGGGAAAAGUAGUUUGACCCUCACAGUUCACAUUCAGCUCAGCAGAGCAAGACCCCAGAGAUGCUUAGAGACAGGACACCUGGCCAUCAAACCCAGUUUGGCCCAGCCUGGUUGGGUGACUUUGUGGGAGCCACUUAACAGCUCUGGGUCCCUGUUUUACCAUCCUGGGAGCAAGGCCCUGCAGCUCCACGAGACCUUUACCCCGGGAAGAAGCCGCCACCCAUGAAAGCAUUUCUGAAGCCCCUUUCUAAGACAAGGCUCAGCAUCUUGAUAUUUUUGACAGAUUCCUCCCAAGUCUGGCUCUGGGAGGUAUGUACCCAUCUCAAAUGUUCCCAAGAUAAAUUCAUCCUUCAGGAAAUGGAAAUGAACUUGCUUACUAAUGUGUGAUUCCUAGUUGUAGCCACCGGAUGUGCUGAGGCCUAAAUGUUAGCAGGUGGGAGGAGGCCACAGAACAAUAAAAACAACCAAAUAAGA